AGACCGGCGACCGCGCCAGCCGCGAAUCGGAUCUCUAUGGAGAUGGCCUAGGCGAUAUCCCUGAGCUGAGAGCAUCACCCUGUCCCCGAAUCCUUCUUUCCUCUCUGUUUUGUUUUUCAUUCCCCUCCCUCUCUCCCCUCCCCCUCCAGUCCACGACGACUGGCUGUUGACCCUGUUCAGGCCUCGGUGAAGGCUUUUGGUUACUCCCCUUCCCACCCCAUCCCUUAAUUUUAUUCUUUUGAAGAGUGCAUUUCAAGCUGCCAAGGUGGAGAGAGGGAUUACAGAAAGGAGAACACCUUAUUUCAGCUUUUAUUUUUAUGUGAUAAUCUACCUUUAAGAAAAGGUGUACCAUACCUGAGAGCACCAGGAAGUCGCAUGAGAGAUCACCUGAUACAUGAACGUAUGAUGUUCCAUCUGCGCAUUGAUGAAUAGGCAGCAUUUACAAAUUAACUGAUGUGUUGCUGUAUAUCAUCUCUUUGAUGAUUGCUCCUCUUCUUUGUAUCCUGUCUUAUAAUUUCAACACAUUUGCGAUACUCAAUGUCUAUUCUAAAUUAACCAUGUUUUGUACCACAAACUCAUUGCCCAUGGAUCUGUUGCUGAAACAAGGAAGUCUUAAACAAGAAGUGGAAUCUUUCUGUUAUCAGAUUGUGUCUGAAUCAAAUGAUCAGAAGGUUGGAAUAUUACAAAGUGAAGAUAAGCAGUUGCAACCUUCAGUUUCUAAAAAAUCAGAAGGUGAGCUUUCCAGGGUCAAAUUUAUAUCCAAUUCCAACAAAAUAACAUUUAGUAAAAAACCAAAAAGAAGAAAAUAUGAUGAAAGUUAUUUGUCUUUUGGAUUUACUUACUUCGGAAAUAGAGAUGCACCUCAUGCUCAGUGUGUAUUAUGUAAGAAAAUUUUAUCAAAUAGCUCUUUAGCCCCUAGUAAGCUUCGAAGACAUUUGGAAACUAAACAUGCUGCAUAUAAAGACAAAGACAUAAGCUUUUUCAAGCAACAUCUCGAUUCACCUGAAAAUAAUAAACCCCCAACACCUAAAAUUGUGAAUACAGAUAAUGAAAGUGCUACAGAAGCAUCAUACAAUGUAAGUUACCAUAUAGCGCUGAGUGGAGAGGCUCAUACUAUUGGAGAAUUGCUUAUCAAACCUUGUGCAAAAGAUGUAGUGAUGCGGAUGUUUGAUGAACAAUAUAGUAAAAAAAUAGAUGCAGUACAGCUAUCAAACAGUACUGUUGCACGUCGAAUUAAGGAUCUAGCUGCUGACAUUGAAGAAGAGCUUGUUUGUAGACUGAAAAUUUGCGAUGGGUUUUCACUGCAACUAGAUGAAUCAGCUGAUGUUUCAGGACUUGCUGUGCUGCUUGUGUUUGUUCGUUAUAGGUUUAAUAAGUCUAUUGAGGAAGACCUACUCCUGUGUGAAUCUUUGCAAAGUAAUGCUACCGGUGAAGAAAUAUUCAACUGUAUCAACAGUUUUAUGCAGAAACAUGAAAUUGAAUGGGAAAAAUGUGUUGAUGUUUGUAGUGAUGCUUCUAGGGCAGUGGAUGGGAAAAUUGCCGAAGCUGUCACCUUAAUAAAAUAUGUGGCUCCCGAAAGCACCAGUAGUCACUGCCUAUUAUACAGACAUGCACUGGCAGUUAAAAUAAUGCCUACAUCUCUAAAAAAUGUGCUAGACCAGGCAGUACAAAUCAUCAAUUAUAUUAAAGCUCGACCACAUCAAUCCAGACUAUUAAAAAUUUUAUGUGAGGAAAUGGGUGCUCAGCACACAGCACUUCUUCUAAAUACAGAGGUGAGGUGGCUUUCUCGAGGUAAAGUUCUUGUAAGACUUUUUGAACUUCGUCGUGAACUUUUGGUUUUCAUGGAUUCUGCUUUUCGACUAUCUGAUUGUUUAACAAAUUCAUCUUGGCUGCUAAGACUUGCAUAUCUUGCAGAUAUUUUUACUAAAUUAAAUGAAGUUAAUUUGUCAAUGCAAGGAAAAAAUGUGACCGUUUUUACAGUAUUUGAUAAAAUGUCGUCAUUGUUAAGAAAAUUGGAAUUUUGGGCCUCAUCUGUAGAAGAAGAAAACUUUGAUUGUUUUCCUACACUCAGUGAUUUUUUGACUGAAAUUAAUUCUACAGUUGAUAAAGAUAUUUGCAGUGCCAUUGUGCAGCACCUAAGGGGUUUGCGCGCUACUCUGUUAAAAUACUUUCCUGUAACAAAUGACAAUAAUGCUUGGGUUAGAAAUCCAUUUACAGUUACUGUUAAACCAGCUUCAUUAGUAGCACGGGACUAUGAGAGCCUGAUUGAUUUAACAUCUGAUUCUCAAGUGAAGCAAAAUUUUAGUGAACUUUCACUAAAUGAUUUUUGGAGUAGCCUAAUUCAGGAAUACCCAAGCAUUGCAAGGCGUGCAGUGCGUGUACUUCUUCCUUUUGCUACAAUGCACCUGUGUGAAACGGGGUUUUCAUAUUACGCUGCAACAAAAACAAAAUAUAGGAAAAGACUUGAUGCUGCACCUCAUAUGCGAAUCCGACUUAGCAAUAUUACACCUAAUAUUAAGCGGAUAUGUGAUAAAAAGACACAAAAACACUGUUCUCAUUAAAAUUGGAGGAGUUUGCAUGUCUCAUGAUAACCAAAUGUAAGAUGAAAAUAAAAGAUGAUUUACUUCAUCUCUGGUAUUUGGGGGAUUUAAAUAAAAUGAUUCCAUUUUUUUAUACUAUUUAGAUUUUAAGAAGGCUAAAGAAUCAAACGUUUUAAACA